ACUUCCGGGGGAGCGGCGCGGCGGCGCGGGAGAAGUCAAAUCCUUCCUGGGAGGAUGAAGAUCUGCCAGCUCUGAGGAUUCUGGCUGGGAAGAAAAAGAGCCUCAAGCUUUGAAGGCCAUUCCCAUGGUAGACAGAGCUGAUGUGAAAAGUGGCCAUCCUGUUGCCCCAGGCACAUGACCUUCUGAAGUGACCAGGCUGAAAGGGAAGCAAUACUCGUGUGAUCUCUCACCCCGUCACUCAGGGUGGCGCAAUCACGACUCAUUGGCUCACUGCAGCCUAGACCUCCCAGCUGGAGCAAUUCUCCUGCCUCAGCCUUCUGAGUAGCUGGGACUACAGUUGGUUCUAAAGAGUGGUGAGUCAGAAGAGACGUCAGGCAGCAAGCGACUUGGGCCAUGGCCUCUGACCUAGACUUCUCACCUCCGGAGGUGCCCGAGCCCACUUUCCUGGAGAACCUGCUACGGUACGGACUCUUCCUGGGAGCCAUCUUCCAGCUCAUCUGUGUGCUGGCCAUCAUCGUACCCAUUCCCAAGUCCCACGAGGCGGAGUUCCAUGUAGAGGCCUGAUUCCAUUCCAGUCAGGUUAUUGGGUACGAAUACCUCAGAGCUGGUGCUAUGUACUCCCUACUGUGUGGCAUCAACAAGCAGGUGGUGUCUGGCUGCUGCACAUUUAGAGAUUCUUGGAUUGAUCGGUGGGUUUAGGUGGUAUCAGCUGAUCCCUCCAUUAUAAAAAUCCGGUCAGUCUUUCACCUAAGCGGUUUUAGCAUCCAUUGAUGGUCGUUGCUUAGAUCCAUUAUUUCCUUCUGCAUCUGUUAGCUGGAAUUCUUUAACAAAGACCUUUUCCUUAUCACUUGUAUGAUUACUCUGAAUUGCUCUUCAUAAUGAAAAGCAGGAAAAAUGCUUGGUUCUUUCCCUUUAUUUAUCAAUUUUCAAAGUUGUGAGUUCAGACUCUAGCAACUUCCAAUGAUGACCAAUGAAGCUUUGGUUUUCAUAGCAUUCUGAACAUAUUUUUAAUAUAUUUAAUAUGUUUUAGUUUUUUUUUUUUGAGGGCACUUAUCUGCCAUUAAUUUGUUUUUUAUGUUCAGUGGGAGCCCCUUUAAGUUGAUGUCUUUGUUCUUUGUCAUACUUCAUUAGUCUUUGAUAGCUUCCUUGCUUCAUGGUUCAAUAAGAUGUCACAGGCUCUUUUUUGUGUGUGUGCGAGACAGGGUCUUGUCUGUUGCCCAGGCUGGAGUGCAGUGGCACAAUCACAGCUCACUGCAAUCUCUGUCUCCCAAGUUCAAGCAAUUCUCCUGCUUCAGCCUCCCAAGUAGCUGGGACUACAGGUGUGCCACCAUGGCUGGCUAAUUUUUGUAUUUUUAGUAGAGACACGGUUUUGCCAUGUUGCCCAGGCUGGUCACAAACUCUUGGGCUCAAGCCAUCCACUUGCCUUGAGCUCCCAAAGUGCUGGAAUUAUAGGCAUGAGCCACUGCGCCUGGCCCCAGGCUCAUUUUGUACAUUUCCUGCCCCAGUCUUGGAAUCAGUCAUUUCUCUAAAAUGCUCUGGUUCUUUUUAGCUAGAAAAUAGUAUCUAGAGGCUACAGUUGGGACAUUAGAAGUUUUCAGUGCUACUGAGCUGUGAUUGCAUCUAGGCCUUUCAAUAAACAGAAAUAGAAAAUAAACAUUUUUUAAGAAAUGAAAAAGUUGUGAGUUCAUACUGGUAUUUCCAAUUCAAAUGUAAGGUGAUAGUGUUUCUAUUUAUUUGAUUUUAUACUAGUGUCUUGUAACUCUUUAUCUUAUGCUGGAAAUCUUGUUCUCAAUAACAUUAACAAAAUGAUGUAUCUGCUAGAUCCUACUGAAUCUGAGGUCCCCAGGACCACCCCAGGUUCAGUGAUGCACUAGGACUCUCAGCUGUGGCAGUGAAAGGAUACCAGGUAUGGCGGCACAGGGAAAAGGUACAUGGGGCAGAGACUGGAGGAAACAGGCGCAGGCGUCUGAGUGCUCUCCCAUUGGAUACCCACAGGAAGGAUUUGUGGCAAUGUGUGUGAAGUGUUAUCUAGCAGGGAAGUGAGUUAGAGACUCAGUGCCCACAUCUCUUACUGAGGACUGGUUACAGAAGCACCCUUGGCCUAGCAUGUACCAAAAUUCCAGACUUCCAGAAAGCAAGCAGGUGUUCAGCAUGAACCUUAUUGUUUACACAGUAUAGGCGUGGUGAGCCACUCUUAUCAUUUCUGGGAAUUGUGAGAACCACCUGGAAUCCAAGUUCCCAGAUGCCAGUCAAGGGCCAACCUUGCAAGCAUGCUUCUCUAAGAUUAGCAAUUUAUAUUAACUUUAUUCUGCUCAUCUACAAUAUACCAGUUACACUUUUAAAAUAACUAUAUUUUUUACUACUAAGACUCAGAAUGAAAUUUAAGACUUCUUUGUGAUUCUUUUUUGGCCUUAAAAUAUGUCUUUGUGGAGAUACAAGGUCAAAAUGUUGUGUUUAGUAACUAUUUUUCUCUGUGUAGGUCUCCCAUCAUGAGAUAUAGUUUGGUUAAUUUGCUUCAAUCUGUUUUUAAUUUUUAGAGAUUUUUAAAAUUUUGAUUUAAUUUGUUGUUUUAAUUAUAUAAAACAUUUAUAUACAAUAUUUCUCAAAGUCAAAACUAUAUAACAAGGUACAUUUACAGAAGUUUCCUUUAAUCUCAUUCUCCUCCACCCUAUUCCCUUCCUUCCCACAUAGUUAACAGUUGUUAUUAGUUUAUCUUUCCUUUGUUUCUUUUUGAAAACAGUAACAAAUGCAUAUAUAUGUGUAUGGUGUGUACAUAUAUAUUUAUAUUCCCCCCUUCAUUAAAUAAAAGAUAGCAUACUAUUAAA